AUCUUCCUGCGGCGCGUUGCGACAUGGAGGGCGCGAUGGCAGUGCGGGUGACGGCCGCUCAUACGGCAGAAGCCCAGGCCGAAGCCGGGCGGGAAGCGGGCGAGGGUGCAGUUGCGGCGGUGGCGGCGGCCUUGGCCCCCAGCGGCUUCCUCGGCCUCCCGGCGCCCUUCAGCGAGGAAGGUAACCGGGCCGACCCGGAGGGUGCGGCCGGGGUGCGGGCAGUUCAUCCCGGGCUGGCAGAGGCCCGGAUGGCCCGAGCUGCGGGCUCGACCGACCCUCCCAGACCCAGACACCUCGCGGAUCUCGCGGGACCCUCACAGCCCUCCACGAAACCCCCAGAUGAGGACGAUGUGCACAGAUGCGGCCGCUGCCAGGCAGAGUUCACCGCCUUGGAGGAUUUUGUUCAGCACAAGAUUCAGAAGGCCUGCCAGCGGGCCCCUCCGGAGGCCCUGCCUGCCACCCCUGCCACCACAGCGUUGCUGGGCCAGGAGGUGGUGCCGGCAGCACCAGGCCCAGAGGAGCCCAUCACUGUGGCCCACAUCGUGGUGGAGGCGGCCUCUCUGGCAGCAGACAUCAGCCACGCAUCUGACCUUGUUGGUGGUGGGCACAUCAAAGAGGUCAUCGUGGCUGCUGAGGCGGAGCUGGGAGACGGUGAGAUGGCCGAGGCCCCGGGCAGCCCCCGCCAGCAGGGGCUGGGGCUCGCAGGGGAGGGUGAGCAGGCCCAGGUGAAGCUACUGGUGAACAAGGAUGGCCGCUAUGUGUGUGCGCUGUGCCACAAGACCUUCAAGACGGGCAGCAUCCUCAAGGCCCACAUGGUCACUCACAGCAGCCGCAAGGACCACGAGUGCAAGCUCUGUGGGGCCUCCUUCCGCACCAAGGGCUCACUCAUCCGGCACCACCGGCGGCACACGGAUGAGCGCCCCUACAAGUGCUCCAAGUGUGGAAAGAGCUUCCGGGAGUCGGGUGCACUGACCCGGCACCUCAAGUCUCUCACCCCCUGCACAGAGAAAAUCCGCUUCAGUGUGAGCAAGGACGUGGUUGUCAGCAAAGAGGACGCACGUGCAGGUUCUGGAGCUGGAGCUGCCGGCUUGGGGACAGCCACAUCAUCGGUGACAGGCGAGCCUAUAGAGACUUCACCCGUGAUUCACCUGGUGACAGAUGCCAAGGGCACCGUCAUCCACGAAGUCCACGUCCAGAUGCAGGAGCUGUCCCUGGGCAUGAAAGCCCUGGCCCCAGAGCCCCCCGUCUCCCAGGAGCUCCCCUGCUCCAGCGAGGGCAGCCGUGAGAACCUGCUGCACCAGGCCAUGCAGAACUCCGGCAUCGUCCUUGAGCGCGCUGCUGGGGAGGAGGGUGCCCUGGAGCCAGCUCCUGCUGCCGGGUCCAGUCCCCAGCCCCUGGCAGUGGCAGCCCCGCAGCUGCCGGUACUGGAAGUGCAGCCGCUGGAGACACAGGUGGCCAGCGAGGCCUCAGCGGUGCCCAGGACCCACCCAUGUCCUCAGUGCAGUGAGACCUUCCCGACAGCAGCCACCCUGGAGGCCCACAAGAGGGGCCACACCGGGCCGAGGCCGUUCGCCUGCGCGCAGUGUGGCAAGGCCUUCCCCAAGGCCUACCUGCUCAAGAAGCACCAGGAGGUGCACGUGCGUGAGCGCCGCUUCCGCUGUGGCGACUGCGGGAAGCUCUACAAGACCAUUGCCCAUGUGCGUGGCCACCGGCGCGUCCACUCAGACGAGCGGCCCUACCCUUGUCCCAAGUGUGGCAAGCGCUACAAGACUAAGAACGCACAGCAGGUGCACUUCAGGACACACCUGGAGGAGAAGCCGCACGUGUGCCAGUUCUGCAGCCGUGGCUUCCGAGAGAAGGGCUCACUGGUGCGGCACGUGCGACACCACACAGGCGAGAAGCCGUUCAAGUGCUACAAGUGCGGCCGUGGCUUCGCCGAGCACGGCACGCUGAACCGGCACCUGCGCACCAAAGGGGGCUGCCUGCUGGAGGUGGAGGAGUUGCUGGUGUCUGAGGACAGCCCCGCGGCAGCCACCACCGUCCUCACGGAAGACCCGCACACAGUGUUGGUGGAGUUCUCGUCCGUGGUAGCUGACACCCAGGAGUAUAUCAUCGAGGCCACUGCGGACGAUGCGGAGACCAGUGAGGCCACGGAGAUCAUCGAGGGCACCCAGACAGAGGUGGACAGCCACAUCAUGAAGGUGGUGCAGCAGAUCGUGCACCAGGCUAGCGCCGGCCACCAGAUCAUCGUGCAGAACGUCACCAUGGACGAGGAGACGGCGCUGGGCCCAGAGGCGGCUGCCGCCGACACCAUCACCAUCGCCACCCCCGAGAGCCUGACAGAGCAGGUGGCCAUGACGCUGGCCUCGGCCAUCAGCGAGGGCACUGUGCUUGCCGCCCGGGCAGGGACAAGUGGCACUGAACAGGCCACUGUGACCAUGGUGUCAUCAGAGGACAUCGAGAUCCUGGAGCAUGCAGGCGAGCUGGUCAUCGCCUCGCCGGAGGGCCAGCUGGAGGUGCAGACGGUCAUCGUCUAGCAUGAGGUCUGCGGGGUCCUGGCCGGGCAGGGACAGGGCAGAGGACUCUGAGCGCCCCACCCAUGCCUGCCUGGCCUGGUAGAGAAGAUGGCACAGGAUGGAGGCGCCCCAAGACGGACAGUGUACAUAAGAGUUUCUUGUUGCUUUACAAUAAAACAUGAGAACCUGCA